AGAGCCAUGCACCUGCUAGCCUUAUCCAAGUCUGGUACAACAUAGCAAAGAGAACAGGCUAUGAAAUAAGAUGGCAAGAAAGAAAUUUAGUGGAUUGGAAAUCUCUCUGAUUGUCCUUUUUGUCAUAGUUACUAUAAUAGCUAUUGCCUUAAUUGUUGUUUUAGCAACUAAGACACCUGCUGUUGAUGAAAUUAGUGAUUCUACUUCAACUCCAGCUACUACUCGUGUGACUACAAAUCCUUCUGAUUCAGGAAAAUGUCCAAAUGUGUUAAAUGAUCCUGUCAAUGUGAGAAUAAACUGCAUUCCAGAACAAUUCCCAACAGAGGGAAUUUGUGCACAGAGAGGCUGCUGCUGGAGGCCGUGGAAUGACUCUCUUAUUCCUUGGUGCUUCUUCGUUGAUAAUCAUGGUUAUAACGUUCAAGACAUGACAACAACAAGUAUUGGAGUUGAAGCCAAAUUAAACAGGAUACCUUCACCUACACUAUUUGGAAAUGACAUCAACAGUGUUCUCUUCACAACUCAAAAUCAGACACCCAAUCGUUUCCGGUUCAAGAUUACUGAUCCAAAUAAUAGAAGAUAUGAAGUUCCUCAUCAGUAUGUAAAAGAGUUUACUGGACCCACAGUUUCUGAUACGUUGUAUGAUGUGAAGGUUGCCCAAAACCCAUUUAGCAUCCAAGUUAUUAGGAAAAGCAACGGUAAAACUUUGUUUGACACCAGCAUUGGUCCCUUAGUGUACUCUGACCAGUACUUACAGAUCUCAACCCGUCUUCCAAGUGAUUAUAUUUAUGGUAUUGGAGAACAAGUUCAUAAGAGAUUUCGUCAUGAUUUAUCCUGGAAAACAUGGCCAAUUUUUACUCGAGACCAACUUCCUGGUGAUAAUAAUAAUAAUUUAUACGGCCAUCAAACAUUCUUUAUGUGUAUUGAAGAUACAUCUGGAAAGUCAUUCGGUGUUUUUUUAAUGAAUAGCAAUGCAAUGGAGAUUUUUAUCCAGCCUACUCCAAUAGUAACAUAUAGAGUUACCGGUGGCAUUCUGGAUUUUUACAUCCUUCUAGGAGAUACACCAGAACAAGUAGUUCAACAGUAUCAACAGCUUGUUGGACUACCAGCAAUGCCAGCAUAUUGGAAUCUUGGAUUCCAACUAAGUCGCUGGAAUUAUAAGUCACUAGAUGUAGUGAAAGAAGUGGUAAGGAGAAACCGGGAAGCUGGCAUACCAUUUGAUACACAGGUCACUGAUAUUGACUACAUGGAAGACAAGAAAGACUUUACUUAUGAUCAAGUUGCGUUUAACGGACUCCCUCAAUUUGUGCAAGAUUUGCAUGACCAUGGACAGAAAUAUGUCAUCAUCUUGGACCCUGCAAUUUCCAUAGGUCGACGUGCCAAUGGAACAACAUAUGCAACCUAUGAGAGGGGAAACACACAACAUGUGUGGAUAAAUGAGUCAGAUGGAAGUACACCAAUUAUUGGAGAGGUAUGGCCAGGAUUAACAGUAUACCCUGAUUUCACUAACCCAAACUGCAUUGAUUGGUGGGCAAAUGAAUGCAGUAUUUUCCAUCAAGAAGUGCAAUAUGAUGGACUUUGGAUUGACAUGAAUGAAGUUUCCAGCUUUAUUCAAGGUUCAACAAAAGGAUGUAAUGUAAACAAAUUGAAUUAUCCACCGUUUACUCCUGAUAUUCUUGACAAACUCAUGUAUUCCAAAACAAUUUGCAUGGAUGCUGUGCAGAACUGGGGUAAACAGUAUGAUGUUCAUAGCCUCUAUGGAUACAGCAUGGCUAUAGCCACAGAGCAAGCUGUACAAAAAGUUUUUCCUAAUAAGAGAAGCUUCAUUCUUACCCGCUCAACAUUUGCUGGAUCUGGAAGACAUGCUGCGCAUUGGUUAGGAGACAAUACUGCUUCAUGGGAACAAAUGGAAUGGUCUAUAACUGGAAUGCUGGAGUUCAGUUUGUUUGGAAUACCUUUGGUUGGAGCAGACAUCUGUGGAUUUGUGGCUGAAACCACAGAAGAACUUUGCAGAAGAUGGAUGCAACUUGGGGCAUUUUAUCCAUUUUCCAGAAACCAUAAUUCUGACGGAUAUGAACAUCAGGAUCCUGCAUUUUUUGGGCAGAAUUCACUUUUGGUUAAAUCAUCAAGGCAGUAUUUAACUAUUCGCUACACCUUAUUACCCUUCCUCUACACUCUGUUUUAUAAAGCCCAUGUGUUUGGAGAAACAGUAGCAAGACCAGUUCUUCAUGAGUUUUAUGAGGAUACGAACAGCUGGAUUGAGGACACUGAGUUUUUGUGGGGCCCUGCAUUACUUAUUACUCCUGUUCUAAAACAGGGAGCAGAUACUGUGAGUGCCUACAUCCCUGAUGCUAUUUGGUAUGAUUAUGAAUCUGGUGCAAAAAGGCCAUGGAGGAAACAACGGGUUGAUAUGUAUCUUCCAGCAGACAAAAUAGGAUUACAUCUUAGAGGAGGUUAUAUCAUCCCCAUUCAAGAACCAGAUGUAACAACAACAGCAAGCCGUAAGAAUCCUCUAGGACUUAUAGUCGCAUUAGGUGAAAACAACACAGCCAAAGGAGACUUUUUCUGGGAUGAUGGAGAAACUAAAGAUACAAUACAAAAUGGCAACUACAUAUUAUAUACAUUUUCAGUUUCUAAUAACACAUUAGAUAUUGUGUGCACACAUUCAUCAUAUCAGGAAGGAACUACCUUAGCAUUUCAGACUGUAAAAAUCCUUGGGUUGACAGACAGUGUUACAGAAGUUAGAGUGGCGGAAAAUAAUCAACCAAUGAACGCUCAUUCCAAUUUCACUUAUGAUGCUUCUAACCAGGUUCUCCUAAUUGCAGAUCUCAAACUUAAUCUUGGAAGAAACUUUAGUGUUCAAUGGAAUCAAAUUUUCUCAGAAAAUGAAAGAUUUAAUUGUUAUCCAGAUGCAGAUUUGGCAACUGAACAAAAGUGCACACAACGUGGCUGUGUAUGGAGAACGGGUUCUUCUCUAUCCAAAGCACCUGAGUGUUACUUUCCCAGACAAGAUAACUCUUAUUCAGUCAACUCAGCUCGCUAUUCAUCCAUGGGUAUAACAGCUGACCUCCAACUAAAUACUGCAAAUGCCAGAAUAAAGUUACCUUCUGACCCCAUCUCAACUCUUCGUGUGGAGGUGAAAUAUCACAAAAAUGAUAUGUUGCAGUUUAAGAUUUAUGAUCCCCAAAAGAAGAGAUAUGAAGUACCAGUACCGUUAAACAUUCCAACCACCCCAAUAAGUACUUAUGAAGACAGACUUUAUGAUGUGGAAAUCAAGGAAAAUCCUUUUGGCAUCCAGAUUCGACGGAGAAGCAGUGGAAGAGUCAUUUGGGAUUCUUGGCUGCCUGGAUUUGCUUUUAAUGACCAGUUCAUUCAAAUAUCGACUCGCCUGCCAUCAGAAUAUAUAUAUGGUUUUGGGGAAGUGGAACAUACAGCAUUUAAGCGAGAUCUGAACUGGAAUACUUGGGGAAUGUUCACAAGAGACCAACCCCCUGGUUACAAACUUAAUUCCUAUGGAUUUCAUCCCUAUUACAUGGCUCUGGAAGAGGAGGGCAAUGCUCAUGGUGUUUUCUUACUCAACAGCAAUGCAAUGGAUGUUACAUUCCAGCCAACUCCUGCUCUAACUUACCGUACAGUUGGAGGGAUCUUGGAUUUUUAUAUGUUUUUGGGCCCAACUCCAGAAGUUGCAACAAAGCAAUACCAUGAAGUAAUUGGCCAUCCAGUCAUGCCAGCUUAUUGGGCUUUGGGAUUCCAAUUAUGUCGUUAUGGAUAUGCAAAUACUUCAGAGGUUCGGGAAUUAUAUGACGCUAUGGUGGCUGCUAACAUCCCCUAUGAUGUUCAGUACACAGACAUUGACUACAUGGAAAGGCAGCUAGACUUUACAAUUGGUGAAGCAUUCCAGGACCUUCCUCAGUUUGUUGACAAAAUAAGAGGAGAAGGAAUGAGAUACAUUAUUAUCCUGGAUCCAGCAAUUUCAGGAAAUGAAACAAAGACUUACCCUGCAUUUGAAAGAGGACAGCAGAAUGAUGUCUUUGUCAAAUGGCCAAACACCAAUGACAUUUGUUGGGCAAAGGUUUGGCCAGAUUUGCCCAACAUAACAAUAGAUAAAACUCUAACGGAAGAUGAAGCUGUUAAUGCUUCCAGAGCUCAUGUAGCUUUCCCAGAUUUCUUCAGGACUUCCACAGCAGAGUGGUGGGCCAGAGAAAUUGUGGACUUUUACAAUGAAAAGAUGAAGUUUGAUGGUUUGUGGAUUGAUAUGAAUGAGCCAUCAAGUUUUGUAAAUGGAACAACUACUAAUCAAUGCAGAAAUGACGAACUAAAUUAUCCACCUUAUUUCCCAGAACUCACAAAAAGAACUGAUGGAUUACAUUUCAGAACAAUUUGCAUGGAAGCUGAGCAGAUUCUUAGUGAUGGAACAUCAGUUUUGCAUUACGAUGUUCACAAUCUCUAUGGAUGGUCACAGAUGAAACCUACUCAUGAUGCAUUGCAGAAGACAACUGGAAAAAGAGGGAUUGUAAUUUCUCGUUCCACGUAUCCUACUAGUGGACGAUGGGGAGGACACUGGCUUGGAGACAACUAUGCACGAUGGGACAACAUGGACAAAUCAAUCAUUGGUAUGAUGGAAUUUAGUCUGUUUGGAAUGUCAUAUACUGGAGCAGACAUCUGUGGUUUUUUCAACAACUCAGAAUAUCAUCUCUGUACCCGCUGGAUGCAACUUGGAGCAUUUUAUCCAUACUCAAGGAAUCACAACAUUGCAAAUACUAGAAGACAAGAUCCCGCUUCCUGGAAUGAAACUUUUGCUGAAAUGUCAAGGAAUAUUCUAAAUAUUAGAUACACCUUAUUGCCCUAUUUUUACACACAAAUGCAUGAAAUUCAUGCUAAUGGUGGCACUGUUAUCCGACCCCUUUUGCAUGAGUUCUUUGAUGAAAAACCAACCUGGGAUAUAUUCAAGCAGUUCUUAUGGGGUCCAGCAUUUAUGGUUACCCCAGUACUGGAACCUUAUGUUCAAACUGUAAAUGCCUACGUCCCCAAUGCUCGGUGGUUUGACUACCAUACAGGCAAAGAUAUUGGCGUCAGAGGACAAUUUCAAACAUUUAAUGCUUCUUAUGACACAAUAAACCUACAUGUCCGUGGUGGUCACAUCCUACCAUGUCAAGAGCCAGCUCAAAACACAUUUUACAGUCGACAAAAACACAUGAAGCUCAUUGUUGCUGCAGAUGAUAAUCAGAUGGCACAGGGUUCUCUGUUUUGGGAUGAUGGAGAGAGUAUAGACACCUAUGAAAGAGACCUAUAUUUAUCUGUACAAUUUAAUUUAAACCAGACCACCUUAACAAGCACUAUAUUGAAGAGAGGUUACAUAAAUAAAAGUGAAACGAGGCUUGGAUCCCUUCAUGUAUGGGGGAAAGGAACUACUCCUGUCAAUGCAGUUACUCUAACGUAUAACGGAAAUAAAAAUUCGCUUCCUUUUAAUGAAGACACUACCAACAUGAUAUUACGUAUUGAUCUGACCACACACAAUGUUACUCUAGAAGAACCAAUAGAAAUCAACUGGUCAUGAAGAUCACCAUCAAUUUUAGUUGUCAAUGGGAAAAAACACCAGGAUUUAAGUUUCACAGCACUUACAAUUUUCCCUCUUCACUUGGUUCUUGUACUCUACAAAAUAUAGCUUUCAUAACAUCGAAAAGUUAUUUUGUAGCGUACAUCAAUGAUAAUGCUAAUUUUAUUAUAGUAAUGUGACUUGGAUUCAAUUUUAAGGCAUAUUUAACAAAAUUUGAAUAGCCCUAUUUAUCCUUGUUAAGUAUCAGCUACAAUUGUAAACUAGUUACUAAACAUGUAUGUAAAUAGCUAAGAUAUAAUUUAAACGUGAUUUUUAAAUUAAAUAAAAUUUUUAUGUAAUUAUAUAUACUAUAUUUUUCUCAAUGUUUAGCAGAUUUAAGAUAUGUAACAACAAUUAUUUGAAGAUUUAAUUACUUCUUAGUAUGUGCAUUUAAUUAGAAAAAGAGAAUAAAAAAUGUAAGUGUA